ACUCAUAGAAACUGGAGGCAAAAUGCAUGACAGUAACAAUGUGGAGAAAGACAUUACACCAUCUGAAUUGCCUGCAAACCCAGGUUGUCUGCAUUCAAAAGAGCAUUCUAUUAAAGCUACCUUAAUUUGGCGCUUAUUUUUCUUAAUCAUGUUUCUGACAAUCAUAGUGUGUGGAAUGGUUGCUGCUUUAAGCGCAAUAAGAGCUAACUGCCAUCAAGAGCCAUCAGUAUGUCUUCAAGCUGCAUGCCCAGAAAGCUGGAUUGGUUUUCAAAGAAAGUGUUUCUAUUUUUCUGAUGACACCAAGAACUGGACAUCAAGUCAGAGGUUUUGUGACUCACAAGAUGCUGAUCUUGCUCAGGUUGAAAGCUUCCAGGAACUGAAUUUCCUGUUGAGAUAUAAAGGCCCAUCUGAUCACUGGAUUGGGCUGAGCAGAGAACAAGGCCAACCAUGGAAAUGGAUAAAUGGUACUGAAUGGACAAGACAGUUAGUCAUGAAAGAAGAUGGUGCCAACUUGUAUGUUGCAAAGGUUUCACAAGUUCCUCGAAUGAAUCCAAGACCUGUCAUGGUUUCCUAUCCUGGGAGCAGGAGAGUGUGCCUAUUUGAAUGACAAAGGUGCCAGUAGUGCCAGGCACUACACAGAGAGGAAGUGGAUUUGUUCCAAAUCAGAUAUACAUGUCUAGAUGUUACAGCAAAGCCCCAACUAAUCUUUAGAAGCAUAUUGGAACUGAUAACUCCAUUUUAAAAUGAGCAAAGAAUUUAUUUCUUAUACCAACAGGUAUAUGAAAAUAUGCUCAAUAUCACUAAUAACUGGGAAAAUACAAAUCAAAAUCAUAGUAAAAUAUUACCUGUUUUCAUGGUGCUAAUAUUACCUGUUCUCCCACUGCUAAUGACAUACCCGAGACUGAGUAAUUUAUAAAUAAAAGAGAUUUAAUUGACUCAUAGUUCCACAUGGCUGGGGAGGUCUUGCAAUCAUGACAGAAGGCAAAUGGGAAGCAAAGUCAUGUCUUAUGUGGUGGCAGGCAGGGGGACUUGUGCACAGGAACUCCUAUUUAUACAACCAUCAGAUAUCUUGAGACAAGAACAGUAUGGGGCUCCCUGGUGUGAUUCCGUCCUGCGCGGCUGUUCUCUGGAGCAGCAUUCAUUUAUCUUCGUCUGCCUUGUCUCCUACCUAAGUGUGUGUCGCCACCCGAUGGAAGAUUCGAUGGACAUGGACAUGAGCCCCCUGAGGCCCCAGAACUAUCUUUUCAGUUGUGAACUAAAGGCCGACAAAGAUGAUCACUUUAAGGUGGAUAAUGAUGAAAAUGAGACCAGUUAUCUUUAAGAACGGUCAGCUCAGGGGCUGGUGCAAAGGAUGAACUGCACAUUGUUGAAGCAGAGGCCAUGAAUGACGAAGGCAGUCCAAUUAAAGUAACACUGGCAACUUUGAAAAUGUCUGUACAGCCAACGGUUUCUCUUGGGGGCUUUGAAAUAACACCACCAGUGGACUUAAGGUUGAAGUGUGGUUCAGGGCCAGUGCAUAUUAGUGGACAGCACUUAGUAGCUGUGAAGGAAGGUGCAGAGUCAGAAGAUGAAGAAGAGGAGGAUGUGAAACUCUUAAGUAUAUCUGGAAAGCAGUCUGCCCCUGGAGGUGGGCAGAAAAAAGUAAAACUUGCUGCUGCUGCUGAUGAUGAUGAUGAUGAAGAUGAUGAUGAUGAUGAUGACGAGGAAGCUGAAGAAAAAGCGCCAGUGAAGAAAUCUAUACGAGAUACUCCAGCCAAAAAUGCACAAAAGUCAAAUCAGAAUGGAAAAGACUCAAAACCAUCAUCAACACCAAGAUCAAAAGGACAAGAAUCCUUCAAAAAACAGGAAAAAUCUCCUAAAACACCAAAAGGAUCUAGUUCUGUAGAAGACAUUAAAGCAAAAAUGCAAGCAAGUAUAGAAAAACGUGGUUCUCUUCCCAAAGUGGAAACCAAGUUCAUCAAUUAUGUGAAGAAUUUCUUCUGGAUGACUGACCAAGAGGCUAUUCAAGAUCUCUGGCAGUGGAGGAAGUCUCUUUAAGAAAAUAGUUUAAACAAUUUGUUAAAAAUUUUCCAUCUUAUUUCAUUUCUGUAACAGUUGAUAUCUGGCUGUCCUUUUUAUAGUGCAGAGUGAGAACUUUCCCUACCAUGUUUGAUAAAUGUUGUCCAGGUUCUAUUGCCAAGAAUGUGUUGUCCAAAAUGCCUGUUUAGUUUUUAAAGAUGGAACUCCACCCUUUGCUUGGUUUUAAGUAUGUAUGGGAUGCUAUGAUAGGACAUAGUAGUAGCAGUGGUCAGACAUGGAAAUGGUGGGGAGACAAAAGUAUACACGUGAAAUAAAACUCAGUAUUUUAAUAAAGUAAAAAAAAAAAAAAAGGUAUGGGGAAAACUGCCCCCAUAAAGCAAUUGUCUCCACCUGGCCCUGCCCUUUGCAUGUGGAGAUUAUUACAAUUCAAGGUGAAAUUUGGGUGGAGACACAACCAAACCAUAUCAGAUGGCUAUAUCAAAAAGACAAGAAAUAACAAGCAUUGGUGAGAGUGUGGAGAAGACGGAACCCUUGUACACAGUUGGUGGGAACACAGUUUGGUGCAGCCAUUAUAGAAAACGUCAUGGAGGUUCCUAAAGAAAUUAAAAAGAGAACUACCAUAUGAGCCAGCAAUCCCUUUUCCAGAUAUACACCCAAAGGAAAUGAAAUCACCACCUCAUAAAGAUAUCUGCUUUCCUGUUUAUUAUAACACAUCUUUAUUCAUAAUAGCCAAGAUACGGAACUAACUGAAGUGACCAUUAACAGAUGAAUGGAUAAAGAAAUUGUCAUAUAUAUAAAACACACACAUUAUAUACAUACAUACAUAUAUAUAUAUAUAUAAAAAAUAGAAUAUUAUUCAGCCUUGUAAAAAGAAAUCCUGUUAUGUUGGGAACAAGCCCCCCAAAAUCUGGCCAUAAACUCACCCCAAAACUGGCCAUAAACAAAAUCUCUGCAGCACUGUGACAUGUUAGUGAUGGCCAUAACACCCACGCUGGAAGGUUGUGGGUUUAUGGGAAUGAGGGCAAGGAACACCUGGCCUGCCCAGGGUGGAAAACCACUUAAAGGCGUUCUUAAGCUACAAACAAUAGCAUGAGCGAUCUGUGCCUUAAGGACAUGUUCCUGCUGCAGUUAACUAGCCCAAUCUAUUCCUUUAAUUCGGCCCAUCCCUUCAUUUCCCAUAAGGGAUACUUUUAGUUAAUUUAAUAUCUAUAGAAACAAUGCUAAUGACUGGCUUGCUGUUAAUAAAUACAUGGGUAAAUCUCUGUUCUGGGCUCUCAGCUCUGAAGGCUGUGAGACCCCUGAUUUCCCACUUCACACCUCUAUAUUUCUGUGUGUGUGUCUUUAGUUCCUCUGGCGCUGCUGGGUUAGGAUCUACCCGACUGAGCUGGUCUCAGCACUGUUAUUUGAAACAAUGUAAAUAAACCUAUAGGGUUUAUUAUAUAUACUAAGUGAAAUAAGCCAGACACAGAAAAAAAAUGUUGCAUGAUCUCACUUAUAGUGAAACUUAAAAAAAAAACCCAAAUACAUAGAAAUAGAGUAGAAUGGUGGUUACCAGAGAUGAGGAAAAUACAGAGACACAGGUCAAAAGAUACAGAGUUGCAGUUACAAAGGGUGAGUAUGUCUAGAUAUCUAACAUACAGUAUGAGGACUAUAAUAGUAUUGCACUGUGUACUGAAAACUUGAUGACAGAUUUUAGAUAUUCUUACCACACAGACAAAAAGAAAUGUAAGUAUGUGAGAUGAAGCUUAUGUUAAUUAGAUUAAGUGUAUGUACAUAAAAACAUCACAUUAUACACAUCAAAUAUAUACAAUAAAAAAGCACAUUGGGAGAUACAUGAUAAAUUUCUAUCUGCAGUUGCUAUUUGCAUUUUUAAAGGAUAUUUUUAUUUUUUAAAUUUUUAGCUGACAACUGUAUAAUUAUGGAAUACAAUGUGAUGUUCUGAUAUAUGUGUACACUAUGGAAUGAUUAAAUCAAACUAACAUUUCAUCAUCUCACAUACUUAUCAUUUUCUGUGGUGAGAACAUUUGAAAUUUAUUCUCUUGACAAUUUUGAAAGAUCCAAUACACUAUUAUUAACUAUAGUCACUAUGCUGUGCAAUAGAUCUCAAAAGCUUAUUCCUCUUAACUGAAACCUACUACCCUGUGACAUGUGGGGAACAUCUCUCUAUUCCCCAGCCCCAGUCCCUAAAUGUUGAAUACACAAUGGGGAAAAAAUAGUCUUCAAUGAAUGGUGGUGGGAAAAUUGUAUAUCCACAUGCAGAAGAAUAAAAUUGGACCCUUACCUCCUACCAUAUAUAAAAACCAACUGAAAAUCGAUUAAAGACUUAAACUGUAAAACUACUAAAAGAAAAUAUAGGGAGAAAGCUUCACAACGUUGGUCUGGGCAAUAAUUUUUGGAUUUGACCUCAAAAGUAGAUGCAACCACAGUGAAAAUAAACAAAUGAAAUUGCAUAAAAUAAAAAAUGUUUCUGCACAGCAAAGGAAAUAAUUAAUGGAGUAAAGAGACAACUUACAGAUUGGGAGAAUAUAUUUCCAAACUAUUGUUGGGGCUCAGAAACGGAUACCCUAACAUAUAGUGAUUUGACAGGUGGAACUAAAGAAGACUCGAGGUCUCUCUGACCUCCUCCUCAACCUCUGUUUCUUAAUCCUCUGUUUUCCCAGAGCACAGGAGGAAGUUCUCUGAAGUUCCUUUAUCUGCUUUAAGUUCAGACUCACCAAAUAAGAAAACAGUUAAUUCUGGUGCCUUCCAUGGGUUUUCAUUAACUGAAGUCAUAUUGUAGGAAAAAGAAUGAAGUCUCUUAACCCACCUGGAUAGAUUUUUCUCACAAACCAUUGUCUUCUCUGCAAGCCCAGUAGACUUUGUCCCAGGCCAUUUAUGUGAUCUUCACCCCAUUAAGUUCUCCCCAAAUUAUUUACUCUUCCCCCAAAAUCACCCACACUUCCCCAUCUCCCUCUCCCCUAAGGACAAGGGUAUAUCACCAUCUAUACCCCAUUGCUUGGUGGGGUGAUCACUCUGAUUCUCUGCAUGCAUUUUUAUAGAUUUGUUUGCCAUUUAUCCUAUUAAUCUGCAUUCUGUCAAUUGUGGCAAGUUAUCAGCAUAUUUUUUAACUUUUAAUUAUUCUUAAUGGAAAGACACUUCUGUAUACACUGGAAAUCUCAGGAAAUUUCUUUUUUCCUUAAGCUUAAUUGAAAUGUUUACUUUUCAGUAAAAUUUCAAGCUUGAGUAAUGUUCAUGCCUGCUUUUCAUUGAAAUAGAAUGAAAAGGUUGCACAAUAUUAUUUUCAUGAAAUUACUUCUAGUAUAAUUCUGAAUAAACACUUUGAAAGGCAGUGAACUGUAAA